AGCCCGGGAAGCUGCUGCGGGGGCGAUGGCUGCGCCGAGCCCGGGGCCCCGCGAGGUCCUGGCCCCCUCCCCUGAGGCUGGAUGCAGAGCAGUCACCUCCAGCCGGCGGGGGCUUCUCUGGCGCCUCCGAGACAAGCAGUCUCGCCUGGGCCUGUUUGAGAUCAGCCCGGGGCAUGAACUGCAUGGGAUGACGUGCAUGAUGCAGGCAGGGCUGUGGGCUGCCACCCAGGUCUCCAUGGACCACCCACCCACGGGGCCGCCCUCCCGGGACGAUUUCUCGGAGGUCCUAACCCAGGUUCACGAGGGCUUCGAGCUGGGCACGCUGGCCGGCCCCGCCUUUGCCUGGCUGCGCCGCUCCCUGGGCCUGGCGGAGGAGGACUAUCAGGCUGCCCUGGGCCCCGGCGGCCCCUACCUGCAGUUCCUCAGCACCUCCAAGAGCAAGGCCAGCUUCUUCCUGUCCCACGACCAGCGCUUCUUCCUGAAGACCCAGGGGCGCCGAGAGGUGCAGGCUCUGCUCGCCCACCUGCCCCGCUACGUGCAGCACCUGCAGCGGCACCCGCACUCGCUGCUGGCGCGGUUGCUGGGAGUGCACAGUCUGCGGGUGGACCGGGGAAAGAAGACGUACUUCAUCGUCAUGCAGAGCGUCUUCUACCCCGCCGGCCGCAUCUCCGAGAGGUAUGACAUCAAAGGCUGCGAGGUGAGCCGCUGGGUGGAUCCCGCCCCUGAGGGCAGCCCCCUUGUUCUGGUGCUGAAGGACCUCAACUUUCAGGGCAAGACCAUCAACCUGGAUGGAACUGGAUACCACCUUCCUCCGGGAGCUCAACGUGCUGGAUUACAGCCUCCUGAUAGCCUUCCAACGUCUCCACGAGGAUGAGAGGGGCCCGGGCAGCAGCCUCAUCUUCCGCACGGCCAGGUGAGCCUCCCACAGGGGCAACAGCGAGAUUGAGGUGGUGAGAGUAAGGGAAAGACAGACAUGGGGGCAUGGGAGUGCACCGGGAGCAGUGCAGCCAAAGACAUGAAGGCUGGAAAGUGCAGAGUUUGUGUGUGUGUGUGCGUGUGCGCGCGUGUGUGCAUAUGUGUGAGUGCAUGCAUGCGUGUGUGUGCGUGCAUGUGUGUGGGUGUGCAUGUGUGCGUGUGUGUGUGUGUAGAGGGGAGGGCUGGAGAAGCCUGGCUGGUAGGGCAGGAGGGGCACAGGUGGACUGCAGCAGGGGACAGAACAGAUGAAGUCCAGUUGGAGAAGAGCUUUGGUGACUAUUUGAAGAAUCUGCCCAUUUUCCAGUGGGGCUGUGGAACCACUGAAGGUUUCAGAGCAGAGAAAAAGACCUAUUUAAUUUUUAACAUUUUUGCUUUUUUUUUUUUUUUUUGAGAUGGAGUUUCGCCCUGUCACCCAGGCUGGAAUGCAGUGGUGCCCUCUCGGCUCACUGCAACCUCUGCCUCCCCGAUUCAAGCGAUUCUCCUGCCUCAUCCUCCUGAGUAGCUGGGAUUACAGGCAUCCCCACCAUGCCUGGCUAAUUUUUUUUUUUUUUUUUGAGAUGGAGUCUUACUCUGUAGCCCAGGCUGGAGUACAGUGGCGCGAUCUUGGCUCACUACAACCUCCGCCUCUCGGGUUCAAGCAGUUCUUCCUGCCUCAGCCUCCUGAGUAGCUGGGAUUACAGGCACACACCAGCAUGCCCGGCUAAUUUUUGUAUUUUUAUUAGAGACGGGGUUUCAUCAAGUUGGCCACGCUGGUCUUGAACUCCUGACCUCAAGUGAUCCACCCGCCUCGGCCUCCCAAAGUGCUGGGAGGCCCAGCAUCCGGCCAAUUUUCGUAUUUUUAGUGGAGAUGGGGUUUCGCCAUGUUGACCAGGCUGGUCUUGAACUCCUGACCAAGAGAUUUGUCUGUCUCUGCCUCCCAAAGUGUUGGGAUUACAGGCGUGAGCCACCGCGCCCAGCCUAAUUUUUGCUUUAGAAAGGGUCCUUGCCCUUUUUAGCUGGUCAUUCCACUUCCAGGACGCUGACGUCAUCAUCAUUGGCACCGUCUUCCUGUCUUCAUCUCAGUAGUGGUAACUGUCAUUCCUUCAUGCUGACUGGGAGCCUCCCUGGGAGGGUAGACUCAUCCCCAUUUGAGAAAUGUGAGAACUGAGGCUCGGGAAGCAGACACAAGGUUGCAGAAUGACUUCUGAGGACUCAUGUUAGUACUUGGCCAGCUACUUCCAUUUCAGUUCCCUCAGGCCCACCCCUGUGGUCGAACAGAAUUACAUAGGAGCUAAGACAGGCACUCCAUUGAUCCAGUGGGUGGACAAGGGGAGUGAAAGAGGAGGUCCAGCCGCCACCCCUCCUGUCCCCUGCCUCGUUCCUACCCCUCAGAGGAAGAACUUGGUAUGGGUGAGACUUGGGUAGAAUUUGGAGUCACUGGCCUUUGGCUGGGCUGGACACGUCCUGACCGGAUGGUGGCAAGCCUGCCAUGGGGCACGGAGCCUCCCACACCUGCCCAUCCAAGUGAGGUCAGCUUUUCCCUUGCCCUCUCCCCCUAGCUGGUACUUAGGCCACCGCUGUCAUUCAGUCAGUGAGUCCUGGUUUGCAUGGAAUUGUUGUGACAUUGAAAUAUUUUCAUGUUGGCUGUCCCAGCCCCACCCCAACCCAGUUCCCAGCCCCUACUGAGAACGCCCCCAUCCCACAUCUCCCCAUCAUCCAGGUAGCCCACAGGGUACCAGCAUUCUGUUCAGACUCUCAGACCACUGAGCUCUGAUUGGCCAGCGCCGGGCAGGGCUUUUUUCUCAUUGGUCUAUUUACCCCGAGACCCAGACAGGACAGGAUUAAAGCCCUUCAAUGACGCCUGAGGACAAAGUUAGGGAAUUGAACCUGCUUCUGCUGGGACUGGGCGCCCUGCCAAAGGUACCUUCUGGUAUGGAAGACAUUUUGAGGCAAAACCAUAGACACACCAUCUGCAAACUGGGGUUGCUGGAUUUUGUUCACAAAACUUCUGCUUCACAACCCUGAGACUUCUGGGGUUGGAUGACUCCAAAGAGAAAUUUAGGAAAUAGACUUACCUGAAGUCAUGUGGCACCAAGGUGCAGAUUCCAGGGUCUGUGUGACGCAAAAGCUAUAGACCAGUGCUACCCAGUAGAAAUAUAAUUCAAGCCAUACAUGUAAUUUAAAAUUUUCUAGUAGCCUCAUUUUAAAAAGUAAAAACAGGUGAAAUACUAUAAUUCAUUUACUCAAUACAUCCAAAAUGUUCAUUUCAUUGAAUCAACGUAAAAAUGAGUAAGAUAUUUUACAUCCUUUUUUUCUUUUCUUUCUUUUCUUUUCUUUUUUCUUUUUCUUUUUUCUUUUUUUUUUUUUUUUUGAGACAGAGUCUCGCUCUGUUGCCCAGGCUGGAGUACAAUGGCAAGAUAUUGGCUCACUGCAACCCUCCGCCUCCCGGGUUCAAGCGAUUCUCCUGCCUCAGCCUCCUGAGCAGCUGGGAUUACAGGCGUCCGCCACCACACCUGGCUAGUUAAUUUUUUCAUUUUAGUAGAGAUGGGGUUUCGCCAUGUCAUGGUCUCCGACUUCUGACCUCAGGUGAUCCACCCGCCUCGGCCUCCCAAAGUGCUGGGAUUACAGGCGUGAGCCACUGCGCCCAGCCUUACAUCCUUUUUUUCAUCCUGUCUUUGAAAUUGAGUAUGUAUUGUACACGUAUAGCACAUCUCAACUAGGAAUAGCCACAUUCAAGGCUCAGUGGCCACCUGUGGCCAAUGUCUACUGAACAGUGCACCUCUAGCCCAACACUUUCACUUUUCUCAGUCUACCUGACUUCACAAACCUGGGCACACAGGAGGUGUGGGAAUGAGCUGGUGGAGGGGUGGGCAGCCUGGCCAGGCUUGCAGAGCCGACUGGCUGGGGCUUCCUGGAGGAGCUGGCAGCUUCACCCUCCUGUCGGCCCCCAGGUCUGUGCAAGGGGCACAGAGCCCGGAAGAGUCGAGAGCCCAAAACCGCCGGCUGCUGCCCGACGCCCCCAACGCCCUACACAUCCUGGACGGGCCCGAGCAGCGCUAUUUCCUGGGCGUCGUGGAUCUCGCCACAGUCUACGGGCUCCGCAAGCGGCUGGAGCACCUGUGGAAGACACUGCGCUACCCAGGCCGGACCUUCUCCACUGUCAGCCCGGCUCGCUACGCCCGUCGCCUCUGCCAGUGGGUGGAGGCGCACACGGAGUGACGGGCGCCCGGCCCCACUCUCCGGAUCUGGACGAUGGGCUCACGCCAGGAACGCCGGUUCCCCCGGGCCCGGGCAUCUCGCCUGCGCUUCCUCCUGAUGGUCGCCAGAGGGCAGCAUCCCCUAACUAAUACCGUAACCGCGCAGUCCCGUUUGACGGUGGUGCCGUGCCCAGCAUCGUGCCAAGGACUCCCCUACUUUAGCUCAUUUAAUCCUCAAAAAAUGCUAUUAUUCUCUUUUUACAGACCAUGAAAUGGAGGCUCAGGGGGUGAAGGGACUGAUCAAGAUCAUUCAGCAAUAAAUGCUGGAACCAGGACUCAACCAUGGCUUUUGGAUUCCGGAGCCUGUAUUCUUAACCACCAGCUCCUGCAGCUUGGUCCUCAUGAUCUGGGCAAGGGGGGAGGCUGAAGGCUGCAGCCCUCUUGUCAUCCAGAUGGGGAAACUGAGGCCCAGAGACUUUAAGGGGCGUAAGCACGGGUAAGUGGCAAGGUCGGCCCUGAGUACCCAGGCCUCCCGGCCCCCUGCUCCUGGCCUGAUACUCUAGGGAUGCAGGUGGGAGAAGCAGGGGUCCUGGGGGCUGCCUGGAGCUCUGGGAGGCAUUCUGAACGGGGUCUACUACUGAUCUCAGGUGAGCUCUGCCCUCCUCUGAAAGUCACUUUUCUCAUCAGUUAAAUGGGGGCAAGGGUCCGUGGUCCGACCAAGGUCUUGGCUUCACAGACAUCACCAGGAGCCUGCAUGCCCCUGAUCACUCCUUCUCCUUCCUCCAGGAAACUCCAGCCUGGCCUCUGACCCCAGUUCAAUCCGACCAUGCCCAAGCCCAAGCGGGCCUUUCCUCCAGAACUGCUCCGGGGCCUGGCUGUGUGACUGGAGCAAGGUGCUAAACCUCUCUGUGCCUCGCUGGUCUAAUCUGUAAAAUGAAGGAAUGGAAACAGACCUCAUUAACUCAUUAAAUAUUUGUUGAGCACCUGC